GAGCUCAGAUUUUAAGGCAGUAUCUUGCCAAUGUUCCCAGCUGAAUAAAGCCCUUCCUUCUACAACUCGAUGUCUGAGAGGUUUUGUCUGUGGCUCGUCCUGCUACAUUUCUUGGCUCCCUGACCCAGAAGCAAGGUGACUGACGGAAGGCUGAGGCAGCCCCUUAGGUGGCUUAAGCCUGCCCUGUGGAGCAUCCCUGUGGGGUACUCCGGGCAGCCUGAGUGAUGAGAUCCAAAGAGCGCUCCUGGGUAGGAAAUUGCCCCAGUGGAACACCUCACCAGAUCAACACGUAGCAGGCCCCCGUGGAGGAUUAACACAGUGGCUGAACACCGGGAAGGAACUGGCACUUGGAGUCUGGACAUCUGGAACUUGAUAUAAGUAUGAGAAAUGACAGAAAGAAACAACAACUGGAAAAGAAGCACUGCAUAAGACCAGGAUGUCUCUGAAAUGGAUGUCAGUCUUUCUGCUGAUGCAGCUCAGUUGUUACUUUAGCUCUGGGAGUUGUGGAAAGGUGCUGGUGUGGCCCACAGAAUACAGCCAUUGGAUAAAUAUGAAGACAAUCCUGGAAGAGCUUGUUCAGAGGGGUCAUGAGGUGAUUGUGUUGACAUCUUCGGCUUCUAUUCUUGUCAAUGCCAGUAAAUCAUCUGCUAUUAAAUUAGAAGUUUAUCCUACAUCUUUAACUAAAAAUGAUUUGGAAGAUUUUUUUAUGAAAAUGUUCGAUAGAUGGACAUAUAGUAUUUCAAAAAAUACAUUUUGGUCAUAUUUUUCACAACUACAAGAAUUGUGUUGGGAAUAUUCUGACUAUAAUAUAAAGCUCUGUGAAGAUGCAGUUUUGAACAAGAAACUUAUGAGAAAACUACAAGAGUCAAAAUUUGAUGUCCUUCUGGCAGAUGCCGUUAAUCCCUGUGGUGAGCUGCUGGCUGAGCUACUUAACAUACCCUUUCUGUACAGUCUCCGCUUCUCUGUUGGCUACACAGUUGAGAAGAAUGGUGGAGGAUUUCUGUUCCCUCCUUCCUAUGUACCUGUUGUUAUGUCAGAAUUAAGUGAUCAAAUGAUUUUCAUGGAGAGGAUAAAAAAUAUGAUAUAUAUGCUUUAUUUUGACUUUUGGUUUCAAGCAUAUGAUCUGAAGAAGUGGGACCAGUUUUAUAGUGAAGUUCUAGGAAGACCCACUACAUUAUUUGAGACAAUGGGGAAAGCUGAAAUGUGGCUCAUUCGAACCUAUUGGGAUUUUGAAUUUCCUCGCCCAUUCUUACCAAAUGUUGAUUUUGUUGGAGGACUUCACUGUAAACCAGCCAAACCCUUGCCUAAGGAAAUGGAAGAGUUUGUGCAGAGCUCUGGAGAAAAUGGUAUUGUGGUGUUUUCUCUGGGGUCGAUGAUCAGUAACAUGUCAGAAGAAAGUGCCAACAUGAUUGCAUCAGCCCUUGCCCAGAUCCCACAAAAGGUUCUAUGGAGAUUUGAUGGCAAGAAGCCAAAUACUUUAGGUUCCAAUACUCGACUGUAUAAGUGGUUACCCCAGAAUGACCUUCUUGGUCAUCCCAAAACCAAAGCUUUUAUAACUCAUGGUGGAACCAAUGGCAUCUAUGAGGCAAUCUACCAUGGGAUCCCUAUGGUGGGCAUUCCCUUGUUUGCGGAUCAACAUGAUAACAUUGCUCACAUGAAAGCCAAGGGAGCAGCCCUCAGUGUGGACAUCAGGACCAUGUCAAGUAGAGAUUUGCUCAAUGCAUUGAAGUCAGUCAUUAAUGACCCUAUCUAUAAAGAGAAUAUCAUGAAAUUAUCAAGAAUUCAUCAUGAUCAACCGGUGAAGCCCCUGGAUCGAGCAGUCUUCUGGAUUGAGUUUGUCAUGCGCCAUAAAGGAGCCAAGCACCUUCGGGUCGCAGCCCACAACCUCACCUGGAUCCAGUACCACUCUUUGGAUGUGAUAGCAUUCCUGCUGGCCUGCGUGGCAACUAUGAUAUUUAUGAUCACAAAAUGUUGCCUGUUUUGUUUCCGAAAGCUUGCCAAAACAGGAAAGAAGAAGAAAAGGGAUUAGUUAUAUCAAAAGCCUGAAGUGGAAUGACCAAAAGAUGGGACUCCUCCUUUAUUCCAGCAUGGAGGGUUUUAAAUGGAGGAUUUCCUUUUUCCUGCGACAAAACGUCUUUUCACAACUUACCCUGUUAAGUCAAAAUUUAUUUUCCAGGAAUUUAAUAUGUACUUUAGUUGGAAUUAUUCUAUGUCAAUGAUUUUUAAGCUAUGAAAAAUAAUAAUAUAAAACCUUAUGGGCUUAUAUUGAAAUUUAUUAUUCUAAUCCAAAAGUUACCCCACACAAAAGUUACUGAGCUUCCUUAUGUUUCACACAUUGUAUUUGAACACAAAACAUUAACAACUCCACUCAUAGUAUCAACAUUGUUUUGCAAAUACUCAGAAUAUUUUGGCUUCAUUUUGAGCAGAAUUUUUGUUUUUAAUUUUGCCAAUGAAAUCUUCAAUAAUUAAAUUAUGUAAAAA